AGACAGAGUGUCCAAAAGCGUGAGAGCACGAAGUGAGGAGAAGGUGGAGAAGAGAGAAGAGGAAGAGGAAGAGGAAGAGAGGAAGCGGAGGGAACUGCGGCCAGGGUUUACCUGUUCUGGAUGUUUCAUAUAGAUGGAGUCGUAUGACAUUUUGCUACUGGCUUCAUUGACUUAACACAGUGUUUUCAAGGUUCAUCCACAGUGUAGCAGCUAAAAGGGGAAGAAGAGGAUCAGCCCAAGGAGGAGGAAGAGGAAAACAAGACAAACAGCCAGUGCAGAGGAGAGGAACGUGUGUCCAGUGUCCCGAUCCCUGCGGAGCUAGUAGCUGAGAGCUCUGUGCCCUGGGCACCUUGCAGCCCUGCACCUGCCUGCCACUUCCCCACCGAGGCCAUGGGCCCAGGAGUUCUGCUGCUCCUGCUGGUGGCCACAGCUUGGCAUGGUCAGGGAAUCCCAGUGAUAGAGCCCAGUGUCCCUGAGCUGGUCGUGAAGCCAGGAGCAACGGUGACCUUGCGAUGUGUGGGCAAUGGCAGCGUGGAAUGGGAUGGCCCCCCAUCACCUCACUGGACCCUGUACUCUGAUGGCUCCAGCAGCAUCCUCAGCACCAACAACGCUACCUUCCAAAACACGGGGACCUAUCGCUGCACUGAGCCUGGAGACCCCCUGGGAGGCAGCGCCGCCAUCCACCUCUAUGUCAAAGACCCUGCCCGGCCCUGGAACGUGCUAGCACAGGAGGUGGUCGUGUUCGAGGACCAGGACGCACUACUGCCCUGUCUGCUCACAGACCCGGUGCUGGAAGCAGGCGUCUCGCUGGUGCGUGUGCGUGGCCGGCCCCUCAUGCGCCACACCAACUACUCCUUCUCGCCCUGGCAUGGCUUCACCAUCCACAGGGCCAAGUUCAUUCAGAGCCAGGACUAUCAAUGCAGUGCCCUGAUGGGUGGCAGGAAGGUGAUGUCCAUCAGCAUCCGGCUGAAAGUGCAGAAAGUCAUCCCAGGGCCCCCAGCCUUGACACUGGUGCCUGCAGAGCUGGUGCGGAUUCGAGGGGAGGCUGCCCAGAUCGUGUGCUCAGCCAGCAGCGUUGAUGUUAACUUUGAUGUCUUCCUCCAACACAACAACACCAAGCUCGCAAUCCCUCAACAAUCUGACUUUCAUAAUAACCGUUACCAAAAAGUCCUGACCCUCAACCUCGAUCAAGUAGAUUUCCAACAUGCCGGCAACUACUCCUGCGUGGCCAGCAACGUGCAGGGCAAGCACUCCACCUCCAUGUUCUUCCGGGUGGUAGAGAGUGCCUACUUGAACUUGAGCUCUGAGCAGAACCUCAUCCAGGAGGUGACCGUGGGGGAGGGGCUCAACCUCAAAGUCAUGGUGGAGGCCUACCCAGGCCUGCAAGGUUUUAACUGGACCUACCUGGGACCCUUUUCUGACCACCAGCCUGAGCCCAAGCUUGCUAAUGCUACCACCAAGGACACAUACAGGCACACCUUCACCCUCUCUCUGCCCCGCCUGAAGCCCUCUGAGGCUGGCCGCUACUCCUUCCUGGCCAGAAACCCAGGAGGCUGGAGAGCUCUGACGUUUGAGCUCACCCUUCGAUACCCCCCAGAGGUAAGCGUCAUAUGGACAUUCAUCAACGGCUCUGGCACCCUUUUGUGUGCUGCCUCUGGGUACCCCCAGCCCAACGUGACAUGGCUGCAGUGCAGUGGCCACACUGAUAGGUGUGAUGAGGCCCAAGUGCUGCAGGUCUGGGAUGACCCAUACCCUGAGGUCCUGAGCCAGGAGCCCUUCCACAAGGUGACGGUGCAGAGCCUGCUGACUGUUGAGACCUUAGAGCACAACCAAACCUACGAGUGCAGGGCCCACAACAGCGUGGGGAGUGGCUCCUGGGCCUUCAUACCCAUCUCUGCAGGAGCCCACACGCAUCCCCCGGAUGAGUUCCUCUUCACACCAGUGGUGGUCGCCUGCAUGUCCAUCAUGGCCUUGCUGCUGCUGCUGCUCCUGCUGCUAUUGUACAAGUAUAAGCAGAAGCCCAAGUACCAGGUCCGCUGGAAGAUCAUCGAGAGCUAUGAGGGCAACAGUUAUACUUUCAUCGACCCCACGCAGCUGCCUUACAACGAGAAGUGGGAGUUCCCCCGGAACAACCUGCAGUUUGGUAAGACCCUCGGAGCUGGAGCCUUUGGGAAGGUGGUGGAGGCCACGGCCUUUGGUCUGGGCAAGGAGGAUGCUGUCCUGAAGGUGGCUGUGAAGAUGCUGAAGUCCACGGCCCAUGCUGAUGAGAAGGAGGCCCUCAUGUCCGAGCUGAAGAUCAUGAGCCACCUGGGCCAGCACGAGAACAUCGUCAACCUUCUGGGAGCCUGUACCCAUGGAGGCCCUGUACUGGUCAUCACGGAGUACUGUUGCUAUGGCGACCUGCUCAACUUUCUGCGAAGGAAGGCUGAGGCCAUGCUGGGACCCAGCCUGAGCCCCGGCCAGGACCCCGAGGGAGGCGUCGACUAUAAGAACAUCCACCUCGAGAAGAAAUAUGUCCGCAGGGACAGUGGCUUCUCCAGCCAGGGUGUGGACACCUAUGUGGAGAUGAGGCCUGUCUCCACUUCUUCAAAUGACUCCUUCUCUGAGCAAGACCUGGACAAGGAGGAUGGACGGCCCCUGGAGCUCCGGGACCUGCUUCACUUCUCCAGCCAAGUAGCCCAGGGCAUGGCCUUCCUCGCUUCCAAGAAUUGCAUCCACCGGGACGUGGCAGCGCGUAACGUGCUGUUGACCAAUGGUCAUGUGGCCAAGAUUGGGGACUUCGGGCUGGCUAGGGACAUCAUGAAUGACUCCAACUACAUUGUCAAGGGCAAUGCCCGCCUGCCUGUGAAGUGGAUGGCCCCAGAGAGCAUCUUUGACUGUGUCUACACGGUUCAGAGCGACGUCUGGUCCUAUGGCAUCCUCCUCUGGGAGAUCUUCUCACUUGGGCUGAAUCCCUACCCUGGCAUCCUGGUGAACAGCAAGUUCUAUAAACUGGUGAAGGAUGGAUACCAAAUGGCCCAGCCUGCAUUUGCCCCAAAGAAUAUAUACAGCAUCAUGCAGGCCUGCUGGGCCUUGGAGCCCACCCACAGACCCACCUUCCAGCAGAUCUGCUCCUUCCUUCAGGAGCAGGCCCAAGAGGACAGGAGAGAGCGGGACUAUACCAAUCUGCCGAGCAGCAGCAGAAGCGGUGGCAGCGGCAGCAGCAGCAGUGAGCUGGAGGAGGAGAGCUCUAGUGAGCACCUGACCUGCUGCGAGCAAGGGGAUAUCGCCCAGCCCUUGCUGCAGCCCAACAACUAUCAGUUCUGCUGAGGAGUUGACGACAGGGAGUACCACUCUCCCCUCCCACAAACUUCAACUCCUCCAUGGAUGGGGCGACACGGGGAGAACAUACAAACUCUGCCUUCGGUCAUUUCACUCAACAGCUCGGCCCAGCUCUGAAACUUGGGAAGGUGAGGGAUUCAGGGGAGGUCAGAGGAUCCCACUUCCUGAGCAUGGGCCAUCACUGCCAGUCAGGGGCUGGGGGCUGAGCCCUCACCCCCCCCUCCCCUACUGUUCUCAUGGUGUUGGCCUCGUGUUUGCUAUGCCAACUAGUAGAACCUUCUUUCCUAAUCCCCUUAUCUUCAUGGAAAUGGACUGACUUUAUGCCUAUGAAGUCCCCAGGAGCUACACUGAUACUGAGAAAACCAGGCUCUUUGGGGCUAGACAGACUGGCAGAGAGUGAGAUCUCCCUCUCUGAGAGGAGCAGCAGAUGCUCACAGACCACACUCAGCUCAGGCCCCUUGGAGCAGGAUGGCUCCUCUAAGAAUCUCACAGGACCUCUUAGUCUCUGCCCUAUACGCCGCCUUCACUCCACAGCCUCACCCCUCCCACCCCCAUACUGGUACUGCUGUAAUGAGCCAAGUGGCAGCUAAAAGUUGGGGGUGUUCUGCCCAGUCCCGUCAUUCUGGGCUAGAAGGCAGGGGACCUUGGCAUGUGGCUGGCCACACCAAGCAGGAAGCACAAACUCCCCCAAGCUGACUCAUCCUAACUAACAGUCACGCCGUGGGAUGUCUCUGUCCACAUUAAACUAACAGCAUUAAUGCA